AGCCGCAUGGAUGGCAGCAGCAGGCCUGCCGGGCCCAGCGCGAGCUCCUCUCCACUGUGCACCAUGGUCCAGCGGUGGCUGCUGCUGUCCUGCUGCGGAGCCCUGCUCAGCGCUGGUCUGGCUAACACCUCCUACACCAGCCCAGGCCUCCAGAGGCUGAAGGACUCUCCACAGACAGCCCCGGACAAAGGCCAGUGCUCCACGUGGGGGGCUGGUCACUUCUCCACCUUCGACCACCACGUGUACGACUUCUCGGGGACGUGCAACUACAUCUUCGCGGCCACCUGCAAGGACGCCUUCCCCACCUUCAGUGUCCAGCUGCGGCGAGGCCCAGACGGGAGCAUCUCGCGGAUCAUCGUGGAGCUGGGGGCCUCCGUCGUCACUGUGAGCGAAGCCAUCAUCUCAGUCAAGGACAUCGGGGUCAUCAGCCUGCCCUAUACCAGCAAUGGACUCCAGAUCACACCCUUCGGCCAGAGCGUGCGGCUGGUGGCCAAGCAGCUGGAGCUGGAGCUGGAAGUCGUGUGGGGUCCUGACAGCCACCUCAUGGUUCUGGUGGAGCGGAAGUACAUGGGUCAGAUGUGCGGGCUCUGCGGGAACUUUGACGGGAAGGUGACCAACGAGUUUGUCAGUGAGGAGGGCAAGUUCCUGGAACCCCACAAGUUUGCUGCCCUCCAGAAGCUGGACGACCCCGGCGAGAUCUGCACCUUCCAGGACAUCCCCAGCACCCACGUCCGGCAGGCCCAGCACGCCCGGAUCUGCACCCAGCUGCUGACCCUGGUGGCCCCUGAGUGCAGCGUGUCCAAGGAGCCCUUCGUGCUAAGCUGCCAGGCGGACGUGGCCGCAGCCCCCCAGCCAGGCCCACAGAACAGCAGUUGUGCCACCCUGUCGGAGUACUCCCGCCAGUGCAGCAUGGUGGGCCAGCCGGUCCGCCGCUGGCGGAGCCCCGGCCUGUGCUCCGUGGGUCAGUGCCCGGCCAACCAGGUGUACCAGGAGUGCGGCUCGGCCUGCGUGAAGACCUGCUCCAACCCGCAGCACAGCUGCUCCAGCUCCUGCACCUUCGGGUGCUUCUGCCCGGAAGGUACGGUCCUGAAUGACCUCUCCAAUAACCACACCUGCGUGCCCGUCACCCAGUGCCCCUGUGUGCUCCACGGCGCCAUGUAUGCCCCCGGGGAGGUCACAAUAGCUGCCUGCCAAACCUGCCGGUGCACCCUGGGCCGCUGGGUGUGCACGGAGCGGCCGUGCCCCGGACACUGCUCCCUGGAAGGUGGCUCCUUUGUUACCACAUUUGACGCCAGGCCCUACCGCUUCCACGGCACCUGCACCUACAUCCUCCUCCAGAGCCCCCAGCUUCCCGAGGACGGUGCCCUCAUGGCUGUGUACGACAAGUCCGGCGUCUCACACUCCGAGACCUCCCUGGUGGCUGUGGUCUACCUCUCCAGGCAGGACAAAAUUGUGAUCUCUCAGGACGAGGUGGUCACCAACAACGGAGAAGCCAAGUGGCUGCCAUACAAGACUCGCAACAUCACGGUCUUCAGGCAGACGUCCACCCACCUCCAGAUGGCCACCAGCUUCGGGCUGGAGCUCGUGGUCCAGCUGCGCCCCAUCUUCCAGGCCUAUGUCACUGUUGGGCCCCAGUUCAGAGGUCAGACCAGAGGGCUCUGCGGCAACUUCAACGGGGACACAACGGAUGACUUCACCACUAGCAUGGGUAUCGCCGAGGGCACCGCCUCGCUGUUUGUGGACUCCUGGCGGGCGGGGAACUGUCCGGCCGCUCUGGAGCGUGAGACUGACCCCUGCUCCAUGAGCCAGCUCAACAAGGUGUGUGCAGAGACCCACUGCUCCAUGCUGCUGAGGACAGGCACGGUGUUCGAGAGGUGCCACGCCACAGUGAACCCUGCACCCUUCUACAAGAGGUGCAUGUACCAGGCCUGCAACUACGAGGAGACCUUUCCCCACAUCUGUGCCGCCCUGGGCGACUACGUACACGCCUGCUCCUUGCGGGGCGUCCUGCUCUGGGGCUGGAGAAGCAGUGUGGACAACUGCACCAUCCCCUGCACGGGUAACACCACCUUCAGCUACAACAGCCAAGCCUGUGAGCGCACCUGCCUGUCGCUGUCGGACCGUGCCACCGAGUGCCACCACAGCGCCGUGCCCGUGGACGGUUGCAACUGCCCCGAUGGCACCUACCUGAACCAAAAGGGCGAGUGUGUGCGCAAGGCCCAGUGCCCGUGCAUACUGGAGGGUUACAAGUUCAUCCUGGCCGAGCAGUCCACUGUCAUCAACGGCAUCACCUGCCACUGCAUCAACGGGCGGCUGAGUUGCCCGCAGCGGCCACAGAUGUUCCUGGCCUCCUGCCAGGCCCCUAAGACCUUCAAGUCCUGCAGCCAGUCCUCCGAGAACAAGUUUGGGGCAGCCUGUGCCCCCACAUGCCAGAUGCUGGCCACCGGUGUUGCCUGCGUGCCCACCAAGUGUGAGCCUGGCUGUGUCUGCGCCGAGGGCCUCUACGAGAAUGCCGACGGGCAGUGUGUGCCCCCCGAGGAGUGCCCAUGUGAGUUCUCGGGGGUCUCCUACCCUGGAGGAGCUGAGCUCCACACUGACUGCAGGACCUGCUCCUGCUCAAGGGGGAGGUGGGCCUGUCAGCAGGGCACCCACUGCCCAUCCACCUGCACCCUCUACGGGGAGGGCCACGUCAUCACCUUCGACGGCCAGCGCUUCGUAUUCGACGGCAACUGCGAGUACAUCCUGGCCACGGACGUCUGUGGUGUCAACGACUCACAGCCCACCUUCAAGAUCCUGACAGAGAACGUCAUCUGUGGGAACUCCGGGGUCACAUGCUCACGGGCCAUCAAGAUCUUCCUGGGGGGCCUGUCCGUGGUGCUGGCGGACAGAAACUACACGGUCACCGGGGAGGAGCCCCACGUGCAGCUCGGGGUGACGCCGGGUGCGCUGAGCCUUGUCGUGGACAUCAGCAUCCCCGGGAGGUACAACCUGACGCUCAUCUGGAACAGGCACAUGACCAUCCUCAUCAGGAUCGCCCGUGCCUCCCAGGAUCCCCUCUGCGGCUUGUGUGGCAACUUCAACGGGAACAUGAAGGACGACUUCGAGACGCGCAGCAGGUACGUGGCAUCCAGCGAGCUGGAGUUGGUGAACUCGUGGAAGGAGAGCCCGCUGUGCGGGGACGUGAGCUUCGUGACAGACCCCUGCAGUCUCAAUGCCUUCCGGCGCUCCUGGGCCGAGCGCAAGUGCAGCGUCAUCAACAGCCAGACCUUUGCCACCUGCCACAGCAAGGUAUACCACCUGCCCUACUACGAGGCCUGCGUGCGCGACGCAUGUGGGUGUGACAGUGGCGGGGACUGUGAGUGUCUGUGCGAUGCCGUGGCUGCCUACGCCCAAGCCUGUCUGGACAAGGGUGUGUGCGUGGACUGGAGGACCCCGGCCUUCUGCCCCAUCUACUGCGGCUUCUACAACACGCACACGCAGGACGGCCAUGGCGAGUACCAGUACACACAGGAGGCCAACUGCACGUGGCACUACCAGCCCUGCCUCUGCCCCAGCCAGCCACAGAGCGUCCCAGGCAGCAACAUCGAAGGCUGCUACAACUGCUCCCAGGAUGAGUACUUCGACCACGAGGAGGGGGUGUGCGUGCCCUGCAUGCCGCCCACCACGCCGCAGCCACCCACCACGCCGCAGCUGCCCACCACAGGCUCACGGCCCACGCAAGUCUGGCCCAUGACGGGAACCUCCACCACCAUCGGGCUUCUCAGCUCCACCGGACCCUCACCCAGCUCUAAUCACACCCCUGCCAGCCCCACCCAGACACCCCUCCUUCCAGCCACGCUCACAUCCUCCAAGCCCACAGCCUCCUCGGGAGAACCACCUAGACCAACCACGGCCGUCACCCCACAAGCCACAUCAGGGCUGCCUCCCACAGCCACACUGAGAUCGACAGCCACAAAACCCACAGUGACCCAGGCCACAACCAGGGCCACGGCAUCGACCGCCAGCCCAGCCACGACGUCCACAGCUCAGUCCACAACACGGACCACAAUGACACUACCAACCCCAGCCACAUCAGGGACAAGCCCCACGCUGCCAAAAUCGACCAAUCAGGAACUGCCAGGAACAACGGCCACCCAGACGACAGGCCCACGUCCAACCCCAGCAAGCACCACAGGCCCAACCACCCCACAGCCAGGACAACCCACGAGGCCCACAGCCACAGAGACCACUCAAACAAGAACGACUACUGAAUACACAACGCCCCAAACCCCACACACCACACACUCCCCGCCUACGGCGGGGAGUCCCGUCCCUUCCACAGGUCCUGUCACUGCAACAUCUUUCCAUGCCACCACUACCUAUCCAACCCCAUCACACCCUGAGACCACACUUCCCACUCACGUUCCACCUUUCUCCACCUCCUUGGUGACUCCAAGUACUCACACAGUCAUCACCCCUACCCACGCACAGAUGGCCACAUCUGCCUCCAUCCACUCAGCGCCAACAGGUACCAUUCCUCCACCAACAACGCUCAAGGCCACAGGGUCCACCCACACAGCCCCACCAAUAACGCCGACCACCAGUGGGACCAGCCAAGCCCACAGCUCAUUCAGCACAAACAAAACACCUACCUCGCUACAUUCACACACUUCCUCCACACACCAUCCUGAAGUCACCCCAACUUCUACUACCACGAUUACUCCCAACCCCACUAGUACACGCACCAGAACCCCUGUGGCCCACACCAACUCAGCCACCAGCAGCAGGCCACCACCACCCUUCACCACACACUCCCCACCUACAGGGAGCAGUCCCUUCUCUUCCACAGGUCCCAUGACGGCAACAUCCUUCAAGACCACCACUACCUAUCCAACCCCAUCACACCCUCAGACCACACUUCCCACUCACGUUCCACCUUUCUCCACCUCUUUGGUGACUCCAAGUACUCACACAGUCAUCACCCCUACCCAUGCACAGAUGGCCACUUCUGCCUCCAUCCACUCAAUGCCAACAGGCACGAUUCCUCCACCGACAACGCUCAAGGCCACAGGGUCCACCCACACAGCGCCAACAAUGACGCUGACCACCAGCGGGACCAGCCAAGCCCUGAGCUCAUUAAACACAGCCAAAACCUCUACAUCCCUACAUUCACACACUUCCUCCACACACCAUGCUGAAGCCACCUCAACUUCUACCACCAACAUCACCCCCAACCCCACCAGUACAGGAACCCCACCAAUGACAGUGACCACCAGUGGGACCAGCCAAUCCCGAAGCUCAUUUAGCACGGCCAAAACCUCUACAUCCCUACAUUCACACACUUCCUCCACACACCAUCCUGAAGUCACCUCAACUUCUACCACCAGCAUCACCCCCAACCACACCAGUACAGGCACCAGAACCCCUGUGGCCCACACCACGUCGGCCACCAGCAGCAGGCUACCCACACCCUUCACCACACACUCCCCACCUACAGGGACCACUCCCAUCUCUUCCACAGGUCCUGUCACUGCAACAUCCUUCCAGACCACCACUACCUAUCCAACCCCAUCACACCCUCACACCACACUUCCCACUCACGUUCCAUCUUUCUCCACCUCCUUGGUGACUCCAAGUACUCACACGGUCAUCAUCCCUACCCACACACAGAUGGCCACUUCUGCCUCCAUCCACUCAAUGCCAACAGGCACCAUUCCUCCACCGACCACGAUCAAGGCCACAGGGUCCACCCACACAGCCCCACCAAUGACACCGACCACCAGUGGGACCAGCCAAUCCCCAAGCUCAUUUAGCACGGCCAAAACUUCUACAUCCCUACCUUACCACACUUCCUCAACACACCAUCCUGAAGUCACCCCAACUUCUACCACCAACAUCACCCCCAAACACACCAGUACAGGCACCAGAACCCCUGUGGCCCACACCACCUCGGCCAGCAGCAGCAGGCUACCCACACCCUUCACCACACACUCCCCACCUACAGGGAGCAGUCCCUUCUCUUCCACAGGUCCUAUGACUGCAACAUCCUUCCAGACCACCACUACCUAUCCAACCCCAUCACACCCUCAGACCACACUUCCCACUCACGUUCCACCUUUCUCCACCUCCUUGGUGACUCCAAGUACUCACACAGUCAUCAUCACUACCCACACACAGAUGGCCACUUCUGCCUCCAUCCACUCAACGCCAACAGGCACCGUUCCUCCACCAACAACGCUCAAGGCCACAGGGUCCACCCACACAGCCCCACCAAUGACAGUGACCACCAGUGGGACCAGCCAAACCCACAGCUCAUUCAGCACAGCUACAGCCUCUUCUUCCUUCAUAUCCUCCUCGUCUUGGCUGCCUCAGAACUCUAGCUCAAGGCCACCGUCAUCACCUAUCACCACACAACUCCCCCACUUGAGUUCUGCAACCACUCCUGUUUCCACAACUAAUCAGCUGUCCUCCUCAUUUUCUCCCAGUCCUUCUGCCCCCUCUACUGUUUCUUCUUAUGUGCCCUCCUCCCACUCCUCUCCCCAGACUUCAUCGCCUUCUGUUGGCACAUCUUCCUCUUUCGUGUCCGCCCCCGUGCACUCCACAACCCUGAGCUCGGGGUCACACUCCUCAUUGUCCACUCAUCCCACGACUGCAUCAGUGUCUGCAUCUCCUCUUUUUCCUUCUUCUCCAGCUGCCUCUACUACCAUUAGGGCCACUCUCCCCCACACUAUCUCCUCUCCUUUCACCCUCUCUGCUCUACUCCCCAUAUCCACUGUUACCGUGUCUCCCACCCCAUCCAGCCACCUAGCCUCCAGCACCAUUGCAUUUCCGUCCACGCCCAGGACCACGGCCAGCACCCACACCGCCCCUGCCUUCUCCUCUCAGUCCACCACCUCGCGGUCCACUUCUCUCACCACCCGAGUUCCCACAUCAGGCUUUGUGUCACUCACCUCGGGGGUGACGGGUAUCCCCACCUCUCCAGUCACCAACCUUACCACCAGGCACCCUGGUCCCACCUUGUCGCCUACCACACGGUUCCUGACCAGCUCCCUCACUGCCCAUGGAAGCACCCCUGCUUCUGCCCCGGUAUCUUCUCUCGGGACACCUACGCCCACCUCACCCGGGGUCUGCAGUGUGCGGGAGCAGCAGGAGGAGAUCACGUUCAAGGGGUGCAUGGCGAACGUGACGGUAACCCGCUGUGAGGGCGCCUGCAUUUCCGCUGCCAGCUUCAACAUCAUCACCCAGCAGGUGGAUGCCCGCUGCAGCUGCUGCCGCCCCCUCCACUCCUAUGAGCAGCAGCUGGAGCUGCCCUGCCCCGAUCCCAGCACGCCUGGCCGGCGGCUCGUACUCACCCUGCAGGUGUUCAGCCACUGCGUGUGCAGCUCUGUGGCCUGUGGAGACUAGCAGGGUCGCUGCCUGCUCUCCUGGGGCUGAAGGACUGCAGAUGACAGACAGGAAAACACCCACCAGCCCCCUUCCCGCUUGUGCCAGCAGCUGCUUUCCUGGUCACCAGGCCUGGCCCCCAAGUGCCCUGGGCCGUGGCUCCCUGGGGCACCGGUUGGAGAGGGGCUGCCAAGCAGGGGCUCAGACUACCACACUCCUGCAGACCCUGAGCCAGCAGAGAGGGACUGAGGCGGACAGUGGUCACGGACCUCCCAGGCACACAGGGCACUCCCGACCACCCCUGCCCACUGUCCAACACCUCCCAGCCCCUGAACUUGGCCCCAGCCCUGCUGGGCCCAGAACCCUGCAGAUGAAGCCACAGAGCAGGCGCUCGACCAGACCCAUCAGGGGCGAGGAGGGCACGGAAACCUGUGCCGAGAUGGGGGCAAGAGGCCCAGGCAGCCACCAGCACAGAGAAGAGGAGAUCCCCAGAGUCAGGGAGGGCAGAGGGUGGCAGCGAGGGCAGGGCAGCCGCCCCCGCUCCCAGCCAGGCAGAAGGCCCCCACCAGCACCACACCCAUCCCCAGCAGCCUGUCCUUGGGAGAGGGCGUCACCCGGUCAGAGACUCCAAAUAAACCGGUUCUUGUCAAGGCA